GGCUCGGGGACCCCAGUCGCCUGGGGUAGAGCUGGAGAGCGGCUGGAGGGGCGCGCCGCCACCUGUCUGCCCUGGCCCCAGCAGCUGUGUGGGGCCCCUGGGGAAGCCGCACGGUUCACAGUCCAGGGGCGGGUGGGGACGACGGAGCCGCUCUCUUGAUACCACUGAAGAGUGCAUACUGAGGGCCCCUUUUGUUCUGGGCGUGGCUCCAGGCCGUGGGUACCAGGCGCUCUGAAGCUGGUAGGGGCAGGUUCCACCGUGCGGAUGGAGGAAGGGUCGUGGUGGGGCUGAGGUCUCUCGGGGUGGGGAGUCAGCCGAGUGUGCUCUCCGGGUGGAAAGCAUUUGAAAGGUGCUUGGAGCAGUGACCGUCCCGCAGGAAGGGCACGGGGCAGUUUGCAGUGUUGUUAAAAGUGCCCAGAGGCCGGGCGCGGUGGCUCACGCCUGUAAUCCCAGCACUUUGGGAGGCCGAGGCGGUCGGAUCACGAGGCCAAGAGAUCGAGACAAUCCUGGCCAACAUGGUGAAACCCCGUCUCUACUAAAAAUACAAAAAUUAGCUGGGCGUGGGCGCCUGUAGUCCCAACUACUCGGGAGGCUGAGGCAGGAGAAUCCCUUGAACCCGUGGCGCAGAGGUUGCAGUGAGCCGAGAUCACGCCACUGCACUCCAGCCUGGCGACAGAGCCAGAUUCCAUCUCAAAAAAAAAAAACAAAAAACAAAAAAACAGUGCCCAGGAGGAGGGGAGUCUUGUCAUAGCUGAUGGGGGACUUCCAGGAUCCUUGAAGUUGAGCCACCUGGAGUGGCCCGUGGUGUGGAACUGGCCACCCAAGCAGAGAGGAGGCUGGGUCAGCAGGGAGGGGUCCCAUGAGGACCUGCCUUGAGGGCCAGGCCAGGAGUGAGGACUUGAAUGUCUGGGUGCUGGAGAGGAGCCCUGGACGUUGGCUGAGUGUCCCCCAUCCUGCCUCUUCUGCCUAGGCUGACUUGGGAUGCCCCACCCCUCCACAAAGAUGCCUGUCCCCUCUGCCCAGCCUCUGGGUCAUUUUGGAGAAGAGGCUCUUCUGGCUAGAAGGUGGUAGGCAAAUGACUGCACUGUCAGGCCUCCCUUGCCUGUGUGCAGUUAGGAAGAUGAGCUCCAUUUCCAAGCACCCUUAAGCCCAAAGACUUUUUGAAACUGGCCUCUGGCUCCUGCUCAGGUCGGAAGCAGGAGGUGUCUGCCAUGGUCACCCCUGGACCCCUGGUCUGUCUCCUGUGUGUCUCCAGGCAGCUGCUGGCUCUGGAGGCAUCCACCCACCCAGUGGGAAUCGGGAUCGUUCACUGAUUCAGCAUAUCUGCCCUGGGUGUCCCUGGGUGUGGCAGUCGGGAAGGCAGGCUCCGGUCGGGAUGGCAGGGUCGGUGGCCCUGAAGAAGCCCCCACCCCAGCAGGGAGGCAGGUAUCCAGUUAGCAGGAGAAAGCAAAGUGGAUGAUAGAUAGCGAAGGGUGAGGGGAUGUCAGGUGGAGGGCACAGCAAGUGCAAAGGCCCUGAUAUGGGACCAGGAAAAGGAGCUGGGGCUGGGCCCAGGUGGAGGAAGAGGCAGCCUGCAAGAGUGCCAGAUGGGCCCCAGUGGGUUGUGUGUGCAGAAGUGCGCUCUGGCUCCCAGGUGGAGUGGGGCUUAUAGGGGUCAGGAACAGAGGCUGGGAGGCCCUGGGGAUGUGGACACAGUUGUCUGAAAGAGAGCUGGGGAGGCCGGGCGUGGUGGCUCACGCCUAUAAUCAUCCUAGCACUUUGGGAGGCCAAGGUGGGUGGAUCAUUUGAGGUCAGGAGUUCGAGACCAGCCUGGCCAACAUGAUGAAACCCUGUCUCUACUAAAAAUACAAAAAUUAGCCGGGCAUGGUGGCGGGUGCCUGUAAUCCCAGCUACUCUGGAGGCUGAGGUGAAAGGAUCGCUUGAACCUAGGAGGUAGAGGUUGCAGUGAGCUGAGAUCGUGCCACUGCCCUCCAGCCUGGGUGACAGGGCGAGACUCCAUCUCAAAAAGAACAAAAAAGAAAAACAGUGAAAGAGAGCUGGUGGCAGCCUGGACCCAAGUAAGAAGGAAGAGAUUUCAUAGGUUUGAGCCGGGGGUGGUAGGGUGAGGGGGUUAGCUGCAUUCCUGGCCCCCUUCCCAUACUGUCCUCCCACUCCCCAACCUGCCCAGCAGAGGUGCUUUGGGGACACUGGCCUCGGGACUCAAGGCUCUCGGAAGUCCCUCAGCUGCCAGUGGGGAGGCUGCAGGGCCCAUCUUUGGUCAGAGCCAGCCUGCAUGCUUCCAUUUCACGGAGAGGGUCUCGUAUAAGUGUUGGUUUGGAGGUGAGGUUCCUCUAUGAAAGAAAGCCUGGAAAACGCCAGAUGGCCGCAUGCACCCAUUUCAACGAAAGGGACACCAGGGCCCUGGAGAGGAAGCCACCUGAUGAGAACUCAGCUUCUCUGGCACAGAUGAGCUCUCAGAGGCAGCCCCAGGCCUCAGUUUCCUCAUGUGAAAUGUGGACGACCCAUCUUUCAGGAUCUUUGCAAGGACUGGGUGGGAGCCCGUAGGCAGAGCACCUGCCGGGGCAGCCACGCGGCUCUCAGGAAGUAUCUGCCUCGGGCAAGCCACUUCCUGCCUCUGGGCCUCGGUUUCCUUCUCUGUGAAAUGGGGUGAAGAGGUUACACUGCUCCAAACCUUGACUCUCCAGCACUGCACUUUUCUUCCUGCAAUGAGCCUCAUGCCUCCUAAAAAUGAGGCGCUGCAUAUCCUUCCUUCUCUCUCUGGCCCCAAUCCUGAGCCCCUUCUGGCUGCCCUUGGAGCCUACAGGCCUUCCCGGCUUACACUAGGUCUCGGCCAGCUGGCUCCAGAAAGGGACCGAGCACCUGGUGGGUGCCUGCCCUCGGGGGCUCGCAGCAGAUGGCAGUGACUGUGGAGUGCAGGGGCAGCAGAGUGGGCUGAGGGAGGCUGGGGUCUGAGUGGGCCACUUGCAAGAAGAGGGGCAUGUGUAUAUCCUUCAGCACUCAAGUGUUGCCAGGCAGGUUGAGAAGAGGUCCAUGAAUCACAGCCAUGGUUGGUGUUGCCUGGCAGCUCGUGGGUUUCUCCCGGGCUUGAUUUUGAGCCGGCACAUGGAUGUCGGUGGCUUGUUCAUCAGCCUGGCAGGUUGGCGCUGUACGUUUAUGAGUACCUGCUGCACAUCGGUGCCCAGAAGUCAGCCCAGACCUUCCUGUCUGAGAUCCGAUGGGAGAAGAACAUCACGCUGGGGGAGCCCCCUGGGUUCCUGCACUCCUGGUGGUGCGUCUUCUGGGACCUGUACUGCGCGGCGCCUGACAGAAGAGAGGCCUGCGAGCACUCCGGCGAGGCCAAGGCCUUCCAGGACUAUAGUGCUGCAGCCGCCCCCAGCCCCGUUAUGGGGAGUAUGGCCCCAGGUGACACAAUGGCCGCAGGCUCCAUGGCGGCUGGCUUCUUCCAGGGCCCCCCCGGCUCCCAGCCGUCCCCCCACAACCCCAACGCCCCCAUGAUGGGGCCUCACGGUCAGCCCUUCAUGUCACCGCGCUUCCCAGGGGGCCCCCGGCCCACCCUGCGGAUGCCGAGUCAGCCUCCCGCAGGCCUCCCUGGCUCCCAGCCCCUCCUCCCUGGCGCCAUGGAGCCCUCCCCACGAGCCCAGGGGCAUCCGAGCAUGGGCGGCCCAAUGCAGAGGGUGACGCCUCCUCGUGGCAUGGCCAGCGUGGGGCCCCAGAGCUAUGGAGGUGGCAUGCGACCCCCACCCAACUCCCUCGCCGGCCCAGGCCUGCCUGCCAUGAACAUGGGCCCAGGAGUUCGUGGCCCGUGGGCCAGCCCCAGUGGAAACUCGAUCCCCUACUCCUCCUCAUCCCCCGGCAGCUACACCGGACCCCCAGGAGGAGGUGGGCCCCCUGGAACACCCAUCAUGCCUAGCCCUGGAGAUUCCACCAACUCCAGCGAAAACAUGUACACUAUCAUGAACCCCAUCGGGCAGGGCGCCGGCAGGGCUAAUUUCCCGCUCGGCCCUGGCCCGGAGGGCCCCAUGGCCGCCAUGAGCGCGAUGGAGCCUCACCACGUGAACGGAUCCCUGGGCUCGGGCGACAUGGACGGGUUGCCGAAGAGUUCCCCCGGCGCCGUGGCCGGCCUGAGCAACGCCCCGGGCACCCCGCGGGACGACGGCGAGAUGGCGGCCGCCGGGACCUUCCUGCACCCGUUCCCGAGCGAAAGCGUAAGCGACUGCGUCGACUCCCCCCCCGCGGCGGCGUCGGGCCGGAGGGGCUGGCGGGCAGGCCCCGGCGGGGCGGCCGGGGGGCCAGAGCAAGACCGUGACCGCGGCGGGCCAGUACUCGCCAGGGAUGACCAUGAGCGUGUGAUGGGGCGGCAGCCCCGGGCCUCUCUGCGGGCCUAGGCUUCUGCCCAGCGCCCCUGCUCAGGGCGAGGGGCUGAGGUCACACCUCGGGCACCUGGACUCCUGGCCAAUCAAGGCUUGCCCAGCUGGGAGGCCCCACACGAAAGACUCUUACCAUUUUAUUAAAAACGCAAGGACCUCAGAGACGUUCUUUUCUGUAUGGACCCUUCCUGCCAUUUGUAUUUUGUCCCAGAGAGAAAGGCUCUUUGGGGGGCCCCUCUCCCCAGGACGUCAGGGGGUGGGGCCCAUAAAUAAAUGGAAGCUGGUUUUGGUUUUUGGUA